AUCAGUGUCUUGCUAUUGCCCACUCUCGUUUCAAAUUCCUGGCCUCAAGCCGGCAAUUCCCACUUCAGCUUCCCAAAGCAAGAGAUUUCAGGUAUGAGUCACCAUGGAAAUUUGGUUUUAAUGUGUUACAUCUAGUUUUAAUAUCUCAGGAGUUGAAUUAAUAAUUCAUCAUCUUUAGAGAGAGUCACCUGCUUCAAUGUAGCAAUUAAUUCCAAGCAAGUGUAUAAUCAGAAUUCUUCAUGUCAUUUUUCUGAAAACACAAGCAGUCUAAUUUUAAGAAAUGGCUUGGUUUUCAACUUAAACAUUUAAGUUUAAUUUAUAGAUUAAUGUAUUAAAAUUUUUAAGGGCUUGUUCUUACCUCUAUAAAUUCCUCAAUCCCUGUUCUUUGGCUAUCAAAUUCUUCUGUCUUUGCUUCUAGUUUUCAGUUUCUGAAAUAUAUACCUACAUAUAAACAAAUUUCUUCCUGUCCCCAAUUUCCAUUUAUUCCAUCUUUGGUUUCCUGAACAGGGUUCACUUAAAUUUAUUAGUUUUCUAAAGACUCCUCUAACUUUUUUUGGGGGUGUGACUAAGGAGUUUGCUGUCAACUCUAUUCUGCCCAUAAUCUUCAUUUCUUAAUUAAAUGAAGAAAGGAAAGAAAAGCUGGAGGGAAUGAAUGAUGGGGAGCCUGGGUGCCCUGAGGAAGGACCCCACUACACUACUGACAAUUUAUGCUGUUAAUCUUUCUCCCAUCCUUCCCCAAGGAGACCUCUGGCCUUUUACCAGAGUAACUGCACUGGGGAAAGGGGAAUGAUCAGACUUUUCAGGGACUUACUGGAUACUGGCUCUGAGCUGACAUUUAUUCCAGGGGACCCAAAACAUCAUUGUGGUCCUCCAGUUAAAGUAGGGGCUUAUGGAGGUCAGGUACUUAAUGGAGUUUUAGCUCAGGUCCCACUAUAGUGAGUCCAGUGGGUCCCUGGACUCAUCCUGUGGUCAUUUCCCCAGUGUCAGAAUGCAUAAUUGGCAUAGACAUACUUAGCAGCUGGCAGAAUCCCCACAUUGGCUCCCUGACUGGUAGGAUGAAGGCUAUUAUGGUGGGAAAGGCCAAAUGGAAGCCAUUAGAGCUGCCUCUACCUAGAUAAAUAGUAAAUCAAAAACAAUAUUGUAAAAACAAACAAAAAACAACAACAAAAACCAAUAUCGCAUCCCUGAAGGGAGUGCAGAGAUUAGUGCCACCAUCAAGGACUUGAAAGACGAACUCUCCUAUUUGGCCCGUGCAGAAGAGAGAUGGAUCUUGGAGAAUGACAGUGGAUUAUCGUAAGCUUAACUAAGUGGUGACUCCAAUUGCAGCUGCUGUGUCAGAUGUGGUUUCAUUGUUUGGACAAAUUAAUACAUCUCCUGGUACCUGGUAUGCAGCCAUUGAUUUGGCAAGUGCCUUUUUCCCCAUUCCUGUUUGUAAGACCCACCAGAAGCAAUUUGCCUUCAGCUGGCAAGACCAGCAAUAUACCUUCACUGUCGUACCUCAGAGGUAUAUCAGCUCUCCGGGUUUGUGUCAUAAUCUUGUUUGCAGAGAUCUUGAUCACUUUUCCCUUCCGCAGGAUAUCACACCAGUUCAUUAGUUCAUUACAUUGAUGACAGUAUGUGACCGGAUCUAGUGAGCAAGAAGUAGCCAACACACUGGACUUAUUGAUGAGACAUUUGCAUGCCAGGGGAUGGGAAAUUAACUAAAAUUCAGGGACCUUCUACCUCAGUAAAAUUUCUAGUGGUCCAGUGGUGUGGGGCCUCUCAAGAUAUUCCUUCUAAGGUGAAGGAUAAGUUGCUGCAUUUGCCCCCUCCUACAACCAAGAAAGAGGGACAACGCCUAGUGGGUCUAUUUGGAUUUUGGAGGCAAUACAUUCCUCAUUCUGGUGUGUUACUCCAGCCCAUUUAUCGAGUGACCUAAAAGGCUGCCAGUUUUGAGUAGGGUCCAGAACAGGAGAAGGCUCUGCAACAGGUCUAGGCUGUUGUGAAAGCUGCUGUGCCACUUGGGCCAUAUUACCUAGCAGAUUCAAUGGUGCUUGAGAUGUCAGUGGCAGAUAGGGAUGCUAUUUGGAGCCUUUAGCAGGCCCCCAUAGGUGAAUCACAGCAGAGGCCUCUAGGAUUUUGGAGCAAGGACCUAUCUUCUGCAGAUAACUACUCUCCUUUUGAGAGACAGUUCUUGGCUGGUUACUGGGCUUUGGUAGAAACUGAAUGUUUGACUAUGGGCCAUCAAGUCACCAUGUAACCUAAACUGCCUGUCAUAAACUCGUGCUUUCUGACCCAUCUAGCCAUAAAGUGGGGCAUGCACAGCGGCAUUCCAUCAUCAAAUCGAAGUGGUAUAUAUGUGAUCAGGCUUGAGCAAGUCCUGAGGGCACAAGUAAGUUAUGUGAGCAAGUGGCUCAAAUGCCCAUGGUCCCUGCUCCUGCCAUCUAGCUCUCUUUCCCCCAGCCUGCACCAGUGGCCUCAUGGGGAGCUCCCUGUGAACAGUUGAAAAAGGAAGAGAAGACAAGGGCCUGGUUUACAGAUGGUUCUGCAUGAUACGCAAGCACCACCCAAAAGUGGACAGCUGCAGCACUACAGCUGCUUUCUAGAACAUCCCUGAUGGACAGUGGUGAAGGGAAAUCUUCCCAGUGGGCAGAACUUCGAGCAGUGCACCUGGUUGUGGACUUUGCAUGAAAUGAGAAAUGGCCAGAUAUGCGAUUAUAUACUGAUUCAUGGGCUGUAGCAGAUGAUUUGGCCGGAUGGUCAGGAACUUGGAACAAGCAUGAUUGGAAAAUUGGUGAUGAAGAAAUUUGGGGAAGAGGUAUGUGGAUGGACCUCUCUUUUUGAGUGGUCAGAAACUAUAUUUGUAUCUCUUAUGAGUGCUCACCAAAGGUGACCUCAGCAGAGGAGGAUUUUAAAAAUCAAGUGGAUUGGGUGACUUAUUCUGUGGACACCACUCAACGUCUUUCCCCAGCCACCCCUGUUAUCACCCAAUGGGCCCAUGAACAAAGUGGCCAUGGUGGCAGGGAUGGAGGUUACACACGGGCUCAGUAACAUGGACUUCCACUCAUCAAGGCUGACCUGGCUAUGUAUGACCACUGCUGAGUGCCUGAUUUGCCAGCAGCAGAGACCAACACUGAGCCCUUGAUAUGGCACCAUUCCUUGGGGUGAUCAGCCAGCUACUUGGUGGCAGGUUGAUUAUAUUGGACCUCUUCCAUCAUGGAAAGGGCAGCGGUUUGUCCUCACCAGAAUAGACACUUACUCCAGAUAUGCGUUUGCCUAUCCUGCAUGGAAUGCCUUAUCCACCAUCAUGGUAUUCUGCAUAGCAUUGCCUCUGACCAAGGCACAUACUUUACAGCUAAAGAAGUGCAGCAGUAUGUUCAUGCUCUUGGAAUUCACUGGUCUUCUCCUUAUCAUUUUGAAGCAGCUGGAUUGAUAGAACGGUGGAAUGGCCUUUUGAAGUCACAAUUACAACAUCAACUAGGUGACAAUACUUUGCAGGGCUGGCGCAGAGUUCUCCAGAAGGCUGUGUAUGCUCUGAAUCAGUGUCCAAUAUAUGGUACAGUUUCUCCCAUAGCCAGGAUUCACGGGUCCAGGAAUCAAGGGGUGGAAGUGGAAGUGGCACCACUCACCAUCACCCCUAGUGGCCCAUUAGAAAAAUUUUUGCUUCCUGUUCCCGCAACAUUACGUUCUGCUGGCCUAAAAGUCUUAGGUCCAGAGUGGAGAGUGCUGCCACCAGGACACACAACAAUGAUUCCAUUAAACUGGAAGUUAAUAUUACCACCUGGACACUUUGAGCUCCUCCUACCUUUAAGUCAGCAGGCUAAGAAGGGAGUUACAGUGUUGCCUGGGGUGAUUGGCUUGGACUAUCAAGAUGAAAUCAGUCUACUACUCAUCUUGAAAUCAGUCUACUCUUCCUUACCUGAUGGAGGUAAGGAAGAGUAUGCAUGGAAUACAGGAGAUCCUUUAGGGCCUCUCUUAGUAUUACCAUGCCCAGUGAUUAAGGUCAAUGGGAAACUACAACAACCCAAUCCAAGCAGGACUAAAAAUGACCCAUACCCCUCCGGAAUGAAGGUUUGGGUCACUCUACCAGGUACAAAACCACAACCUGCUGAGGUGCUUGCUGAAGAGACACAGGGAAUACAGAAUGGGUAGUAGAACAAGGUUGUCAUCAGUACUGACUAUGACCACCAUUACCAGUUGCAGAAAUGAGAACUGUAAUUCUCAUGAGUAUUUCCUCCUUAUUUCGUUAAGAACAUGUUUAUGCAUGUAUACAGUUUGUCUAAGAAAAUAUCUUCAUUUUCCUUUUUCCUUUAUCAUGUGACAUAAAAUUUAUUGACUUCAUAUCAGCAUUUAAGUGGUAACUUUAUGUAAUAGCAUUUAGUUUAAGGAUUAAUGUGCUUCCAGCUUUACAAAGGAUAGGGAUAGCUGUAUUAUGUUAGGCAUAAUUAUGACCUUAUUAUUGUCUUUAUUUGAAGAUUAUGUAUGAUUUCAGGAGAUGUAUAUGCGUUCAAGUUGACAAAAGGUAGACUUCUGAUGGUUAAUAUUGAGUGUCAACUUGAUUGGAUUGAAGGAUGCAAAGUAUUGUUCCUGGCUGUGUUGUGAGGGUGUUGCCAAAGGAGAUUAACAUUUGAGUCAGCGGACUGCGAGAGGAGGACCCACCCUCAAGCUGGGUGGGCACAAUCUAAUCAGCUGCCAGCAUGGAUAGAAUAAAAGCAGGCAGAAGAACAUGGAAGUACUGGACUGGCUGAGUCUUCCAGCCUCAUCUUUCUCCUGUGCUGGAUGCUUCCUGCCCUCAAACAUCAGACUCCAAGUUCUUCAGCUUUUGGACUCUUGGACCUACACCAGUAGUUUGCCAGAGGCCCUUGGACCUUUGGUCAAAGGCUGAAGGCUGCACUGUUGGCUUCGCUACUUUUGAAGUUUUGGGACUUCAACUGGCUUCCUUGCUUCUCAGCUUGCAGAUGGCCUAUUGUGGAAUUUCACCUUAUGAUCGUAUGUGACGAAGGAGUUUCCUGUCAACUCUAUUCUGCCCAUAAUCUUCAUUUCUUAAACGAAGAAGGAAAAGAAAAGCUGGAGUGAAAAGUUUUGAAAGAGAAAAAAUUGAUCUCUGUAAUAAUUUUCAAGAAUUUUUACUGCAACUAAAAUUCAGUGUUUAGUUUAUGAAGAAAAAAAUGAAUGGCUAUAGUACAUACAUUUCCAUGGUAACAGAAGUGCUAAAUACGGUAUUAAAAAUGGCAAGAUAUGCCUGUAAUCCCAGCACUUUGGGAGGCCGAGAUGGGCGGAUCAUGAGGUCAGGAGAUUGAGACCAUCCUGGCUAACACUGUAAAACCCCUUCUCUACUAAAAAUACAAAAAAUUAGCCGUGCGUGGUGGCGGGCGCAUGUAGUCCCAGCUACUCGGGAGGCUGAGGCAGGAGAAUGGCAUGAACCCAGGAGGCGGAGCUUGCAGUGAGCCGAGAUCGCACCACUGCACUUCAGCCUGGGCUACACAGUGAGACUCCGCCUCAAAAAAAAAAAAAAAAAAAAGGCAAGUUGUUUAUAUAGGAUUUAUAUUGCAAGAAAAAGAAGAAGGGGAAACAAGAUUUAAUAGAUUUAGUGGCUGGGUACAGUGGCUGAUGCUUAAAAUCCACCACUUUGGGAGGUCGAGGUGGGCGUGAGAGGUGACAGCUGCUGGCAGUCCUCACAGCCCUUGCUCGAUCUGGGCGCCUCCUCUGCCUGGGCUCCCACUUUGGCGGCACUUGAGGAGCCCUUCAGCCCGCCGCUGCACAGUGGGAGCCCCUUUCUGGGCUGGCCAAGGCCAGAGCUGGCUCCCUCAGCUUGCGGGGAGGUGUGGAGGGAGAGGUGCAGGCGGGAACCGGCGCUGCGUGCGGUGCUUGCAGGCCAGUGCGAGUUCCGGGUGGGCGUGGGCUCGGCAGACCCUGCACUCGGAGCAGCCCGCCGGCCCCACUGGCCCCGGGCAGUGAGGGGCUUAGCACCUGGGCCAGCAGCUGCUGUGCUCAAUUUCUCGCGGGGUCUUAGCUGCCUUCCCGCAGGGCAGGGCUGGGGCCUGCAGCCUGCCACGCCUGAGCCUCCCCCCCGGCCUCCGUGGGCUCCUGUGCUGCCUGAGCCUCCCCGACGAGCACUGCCCGCUGCUCCAGGGCGCCCAGUCAACCACCCAAGGGCCGAGGAGUGCGGGCACAAGGGGCGAGACUGGCAGGCAGCUCCACCUGCAGCCCCGGUGCGGGAUCCACUGGGUGAAGCCAGCUGGGCUCCUGGGUCUGGUGGGGACUUGGAGAACCUUUUUGUCUAGCUAAGGGAUUGUAAAUACACCAAUGGGCACUCUGUAUCUAGCUCAAGGUUUGUAAACACACCAAUCAGCACCCUGUGUCUAGCUCAGGGUUUGUGAAUGCACCAAUAGACACUCUGUAUCUAGCUACUCUGGUGGGGCCUUGGAGAACCUUUAUGUGGACACUCUGUAUCUAGCUAAUCUGGUGGGGAGGUGGAGAACCUUUGUGUCUAGCUCAGGGAUUGUAAACGCACCAAUCAGCACCCUGUCAAAACAGACCACUGGGCUCUACCAAUCAGCAGGAUGUGGGUGGGGCCAGAUAAGAGAAUAAAAGCAGGCUGCCUGGGCCAGCAGUGGCAACCUGCUCGGGUCCCGUUCCACACCGUGGAAGCUUUGUUCUUUCGCUCUUUGCAGUAAAUCUUGCUGCUGCUCACUGUUUGGGUCCACACUGCAUUUAUGAGCUGUAACACUCACAGCGAAGGUCUGCAGCUUCACUCCUGAGCCAGCGAGACCACGAACCCACCAGAAGGCCGAACACAUCUGAACAUCAGAAGGAACAAACUCCGGACACGCUGCCUUUAAGAACUGUAACACUCACCUGAGAGUCCGCAGCUUCAUUCUGGAAGUCAGUGAGACCAAGAACCCACCAAAUUCCGGACACAGGAGGAUCACUUGAGGCUGAGUUCGUGACCAGCCUGGGCAACAGGGAGACCCUAUCUCUACAAAAAUAAAAACUUAGCUGGGGAUGGUGGUUCAUGCCUGUAGUUCCAGCUAAAAUAUAUGUAUUUUUUAUUAGUCAAUUUAAAUAAGUAAAUAGAUAAUAAAAAUUUUAAAAAGAGACAAGAGAAUGGCGGUUACAUGGGCCAGUUGACUUGUGAAAAUUCAUUAGACUGGACACUUGUCAUCAAACUAUGUAAUUAUACAUUUUUCUGCAUGAAUAUUUUCAAUUAAAAGUUUAUUAAGAAAAGAUGGAGCCAUUGCAAUGUAUGGAUCUUGAUUCUAAUAAAAAGGCAUUUUUUAAAGCCCUUUUUGCAAUUGGGAAA